AGUGUGCUCCCCGCCCCCUGCCGCGGCGCCUCGCCUCCCGGCUCACCUCCCCACCCCACCUGCCCGCUGCGGCUCUCCGCGGGAGAUCUCACCGUUCUGGAGACAGGGCUCGCUCGCUCUCACGGUAGGCUGGAAGAACGGGCUGUCUGGGCCUUAGGAAAGGCCCAUGCUGUAUAAGGCAUGGGGAAAGGAAAGGAAGAAAGGCAACGAACAAGAAGGAGGGCUUCCAACUGCAGCUUCCUGCCGGCUGCAGGCCUCCCUUCCUAAGCUGAGCUGAGGCUUCCUCUCCAUGGGCUGGGGAGGGGGCGCCAGGAGGCCUCGGCGGGUCCGCAAUUGGCCGGGACAGCUUCUCACGAAAGGUCCUGGGCCGGCAUCAUCAGCCUCACCUGGGAACUGGUUAGAACUACAAAUUCCCUCGGCCCCACCCAGACCGACGCCAAGGGCAGCUGUGGAGUGGGGCGCGGCAAUGCGCCCCUUAACAGCCCUCCAGGCUUCUUAGCCCGGGCUUGGACAGCCGCCUUCCGGCCAGAGGGGAUGAGGUUGCGCUGCGCUCCGGGAGCGCCGAUGGCGUGACUGGCCCCGCGCGGAGCAGCGACAGUAAGGCUGUGUGGGGGGAGCUGGGACCUAAGCCGCGCGCACACCCCUUUCUCUGCGUCUGGUGGAGGUGCACAGAGGCUUUUGAGUCAGGCCCAAGCGCAGCCAGGUGACCUCCCCGCGGCCUUUCAAGCCUGAGCUCGGUGGACAGCUCCCUCUCCCGUGAGUCCCGCUGUCCUGUACGCGCCCGGUCGAGCCCCGGGCUGCGCACCCCGCUAGGAGGUGGGUACUCGUCCUCCAGGAGUUGCCGGUGAGCCCUUGACCGUGGCAGGUCCCCUCCAGCCGCGAGCGACCCCUCAGUACCUGCCGAUGCCUGCUGGUCUCUGGCAUCCUCCAGUCGAGGGUCAGGGUCAGGGAGCAAGGCCUCACGCGGGCGCCCUCCUUGCAGCUGCCCGGCCAGCCCGCUUCUCUGCCCGGAGCCAUGAAUCUCAGUAGCGCCAGUAGCACGGAGGAAAAGGCAGUGACGACCGUGCUCUGGGGCUGCGAGCUCAGUCAGGAGAGGCGGACUUGGACCUUCAGACCCCAGCUGGAGGGGAAGCAGAGCUGCAGGCUGUUGCUUCAUACGAUUUGCUUGGGGGAGAAAGCCAAAGAGGAGAUGCAUCGCGUGGAGAUCCUGCCCCCAGCAAACCAGGAGGACAAGAAGAUGCAGCCGGUCACCAUUGCCUCACUCCAGGCCUCAGUCCUCCCCAUGGUCUCCAUGGUAGGAGUGCAGCUUUCUCCCCCAGUUACUUUCCAGCUCCGGGCUGGCUCAGGACCCGUGUUCCUCAGUGGCCAGGAACGUUAUGAAGCAUCAGACCUAACCUGGGAGGAGGAGGAGGAAGAAGAAGGGGAGGAGGAGGAAGAGGAAGAGGAAGAUGAUGAGGAUGAGGAUGCAGAUAUAUCUCUGGAGGAGCAAAGCCCUGUCAAACAAGUCAAAAGGCUGGUGCCCCAGAAGCAGGCGAGCGUGGCUAAGAAAAAAAAGCUGGAAAAAGAAGAAGAGGAAAUAAGGUAACUCUUUCUACCUAUUAAAUUAGCCAAAGUCUCCAGCUGAGAUAUACAGUGUUAGAAAGAAUACUGUGCUGUUGGGAUGUACGUGUACAAAUGUACACACGGUGUGUCUACCUGCACUCGCAGGCACAUGGGUAUGGAAGUGCUGAAGGGUGGCAUCACCUUUCUGGAAGAGCAUUACAACGUUCUUAUCUUGGGAUCUAAUUCCAGUGAAGGCAAUUCCUUCCACAGAAUUCCAUCCAAAUUUCAGGGGAAAUUACCUGCACUAAGAUGCUUCUCACGGCCAGGCUUGGUGGCCCACGCCUGUAAUCCCAGCACUUUGGGAGGCUAAGGCAGGCAGAUCACUUGAGGUCAGGAGCUCGAGACUAGCCUGGUCAACAUGAUGAAACCCUGUCUCUACUAAAAACACAAAAAUUAACCGAGCCUGGUGGCAUUCUUGUAAUCCCAGCUACUCAGGAGGCUGAGGCAUGAGAAUUGCUUGAGCCCGGGGAAAAGUUGCAGUGAGCCGAGAUCGUGCCACUGCGCUCCAGCCUGGAUGACAGAGCGAGACUCAGUCUGAAAAAACAAAAUUUUAAAAAGACGCUUAUGGCAUUAUUUGAAUAGUGAAAAAAUGGAAGCAUUCUAAAUGUCUACCAAUAUAACAAUUCACUAAGCUACAUCCCUCUUCUCAAUGGAAUAUUACAUAAUGCUUAUGAAGAAUAUAGCAACCUGGAAAGUAUGUGUAUAGUUUUGGUUUGUUUGUUUAAUGAGACAGGGUUUUGCUCUGCCACCCAGGCUGGAGUGUGAUGGCACAAUCAUGGCUCACUGCAGCCUUAGCUUCCUGGGCUCAAGCAAUCCUCCCACCUCAGCUUUCCAAGUAGCUAGGACUAUAGGCACGUGCCACUAUGCAUGGCUAACUUUUAAGUUUUGUGUAGAGACAGGGUCUUUCUAUGUUGCCCAGGCUGAUCUCAAACUCCUGACCUCAAGCAAUCCUCCUGCCUCAGCCUCCCAAAGCACUGGAAUUACAAGUGUGAGCCUCUGCACCUGAUAAGAAUAUUGAUAGUUCAUACAGCAGGACAUAAAGUCAUUUUUAUUUUAUUUCACAUAUUUUUAAAAAGAGUUUGACCAGGCCGGGUACGGUGGCUCACGCCUGUAAUCCCAGCACUUUGGGAAGCCAAGGUGGGAGGAUCACUUGAGGUCAGGAGUUCAAGACCAGCCUUGCCAACAUAGCAAAACCCUGUCUCUACUAAAAUACAAAAUUCAGCUGGGCGUGGUGGCAUGUGCCUGUAAUCCCAGCUACUCGGGAGGCUGAGGCAGGAGAAUCACUUAGACCCGGAAUGCGAAGGAUGCAGUGAACCAAGAUCACACCACUGCACACCAGCCUGGGCAACAGAGCAAGACUCCAUCUCAAAAAAAAAAAAAAAAGUUUGACCAAGAAAAAAAUAAUAACCCUGAAAGAAAAUACACCAAAAUGUUUAGUGUGGGCAGUAAAGAAAACUAUAAGUAAUGUA